GAGGUACGGCCUCCCGGGGACCUUCCAGACUGGUCGGCGCAAGCGAAGGGCGGGGACCACCGAAGGAGUGUGUGACUUAGGCAUCCAGCGCACUGCCUGACCCGAAGUACCGACCCGAGUUAUGCCCACCCUCCAACUUUGCGACGGAAAUGUGUCAUCGAAAGCCAGGUACACCAGGGGUUGGAAAAACCACACUAGGCAAAGAACUUGCGUCAAAAUCAGGACUGAAAUACAUUAAUGUGGGUGAUUUAGCUCGAGAAGAGCAAUUGUAUGAUGGCUAUGAUGAAGAGUAUGACUGUCCCAUUUUAGAUGAAGACAGAGUAGUUGAUGAGUUAGAUAACCAAAUGAGAGAAGGUGGAGUUAUUGUUGAUUACCAUGGUUGUGAUUUCUUCCCUGAACGCUGGUUUCAUAUAGUUUUUGUGCUGAGAACAGAUACCAAUGUAUUGUACGAAAGACUUGAAACAAGGGGUUAUAAUGAGAAGAAACUAACAGACAAUAUUCAGUGUGAGAUUUUUCAAGUUCUUUAUGAAGAAGCCACAGCAUCCUACAAGGAAGAAAUCGUGCAUCAGCUGCCCAGUAAUAAACCAGAAGAGCUAGAAAAUAAUGUAGAUCAGAUCUUGAAAUGGAUUGAGCAGUGGAUCAAAGAUCAUAACUCUUGACUUAUAAGGCUAGCUACUUAAUAAUCACUCUUGUUGAUAUCUCUGCCGACAUCAUAGAAAUUGUUCAAGUGUCAGUAACACUUUAUUAAAAUCAUGUUGCAGAACCAGCAGGUGGAUAGUAUAUAGGUUUAUGCCUGUGUUUCUUUUUCUCCAUGAGAAAGCUAAACAUGAAAUAUAAUGAAUAUAGUAUUAUUAAGGAUUGAGACAAAAACUGUGAUUUUAAUACUUAAAUUGCUAAAGAAUAAAUAAAUCUGACAAAAUGGGUGGAUAUCUUUUAAGUUUAUUACAGAAAAAAAUGCAGAUGAUCUCUUAAAAUAAAACUAAAGAUAAAGCAACAGAGUAUUCCUUUUUUCUUUCUUUAAAUUAGAAAAAAAGUUAAGUGUUGUACUCGAUACAAAGUUCAAAAGGUACAAAAGAGCAUGUUGAAAAGUUAGGUCUCCCUUCCAGACCACCCUAUCCCCAGGCACCCCAGGUUCCUUCCCUUUAGGAAAUAAUGUUACUGGUUUCCUAUAUGUCUUUUUAGAGGUUUUAUGCCUGCACAGUGUAUAUGUACAUGUGUACAUUUUUUAAAGAAUAUAACAGUAUAUUAUGCACACUAUUCUGUACCUUUCUUUUUUCACUUACUAUAUUUGAAGAUUAUAUCAUCUCAGUACAGACCUCCCUGUUCUUUUUUUUAGUUGAGAUAGAUAUACAUAUCAUACAAUAAAAUUUACCAUUUUGAAGUGUAUAAUCAGAACCGGGUAUGGUGGCUUAUGCCUGUAAUCCCAGCAAAUGGGGAGGCUGAGGUGGAGAAUCGCUUGAGGCAGGAGUUCAAGACCAGCCUGGGCAACAUAGUGAGACCUUAGACUCUAAAAAUAAACAUAAAUAAAAUUUAUAAUCCGUUGGUUUUUAGCUUAUUAACAAGGUUAUGUAACUGUCACCACUGUGGAGGAAGCAGUGAUGAUAAAGGGAACUCCUAUACCCUUUAGCAGUCACUCUCUAUUCUUUCCUCCUCAUCCCCUUGCAGUCACUAGUCUACUUUCUGUCUCUAUGGAUUUGCAUAUUCUGGAUAUUUCAUAUAAAUGGGAUUAUACAGUA